GGCUCCGCGGGCGGAAGAGGCGGCGGCGGCGGCAGAAGCGGCGGCGGCGGCGGCGGGAGCCGAGGAGGAGGUUCCGGACGCUGCUUAGGAACCGGGGACUCAGGAGUGCCCGCGCCCUGAGCGCUCAGCUCCAGAGGCGGUGAGAGGGGCGGAGAGGAGACAUGUCGCGGGGAAGGGGCAGAUUUCGGGGUCUAGGCUUGGAGGGGCAACGAUCUGGGACACCGGGGGCCAGACGGGGAGUGUGGGGACCCCGGACGAGUCCACUUUGUGUCAGGCCUCACGGGGUCCGUCCCUCGGUCGGUGCGUCCCGAGCGCCGAGCGUGUGCUGGAGGCGGCGUGGCUCCGGCCAGCCCGUUCCACGCUGAACGGCAGUUUGGGAGUCGGACCGGGGCCUGUGGAUUAGGAUGCAGCCUGCUUCCCGCCCAGCCGGCUCGGCCAGGCCAGCGCCCGCCCCUCCCUCCCCGCUCAGGCUUCGGACUCGCCUCCGCUGGCGGUCUCCCGGCCCAGCCCUGUCUCGGUUCCGCGGGCGGCUGGUACCAUGUGCCCUCACCCCCAGCUCACUGCACCUGGGGAAGAGGUGGGCUUGGCGGAAAGCUUGUCCAGAGGGAAGGAGGAGCUGGGGGUGUAGAGAAGUGAUGUAUAUCUAACGUAAAAACCCUUAUUAAUUUCAUAUAAUCCGUGUCAAAACUGACAGGGAAACACGCACACCUAUAAGGCACGCCAGCACACACAGUGACACACACCCAUGUGACUUAUACACAUAGUCUAGCACACUCCAAAUCACAAACGUCCCUGGACUACGCAUCCGGCCGCCCACCACACCCCCACUCUGUGGGGUGGGGCAUCCCAUGAGGAGUCUUCUGAACUGCGGGCUCCAAGUCAUCAGUCCGACAGGACAGCUGAGUGGACAGAAAGGGCCACUGUCCCCAAAUCCAUCCUGAUUUUCUGGCAGCUUUUCCCAGCCCCAUGGUUUCAGAUUGUUCCUCUUUAAAACUGUGGGGAAAGAUGGGAGAAAAUCUUGGUCUCAUUCCUCUAACACAAGGAGACAGGAUUUUGCGGACUAAUGAGGGUAGGGGCUUCUGGUGGCUUCUCUUCCUGGGUCCAGUUAGGGCUUAGCGUGCUGGGAGUGGCUAGUUUCUGGGUAAGAGUGGCCAAGGGAUGGAGGAGGAGGGGGUGGAAGAAACGGAGAGGAAAAAGAAUGGGUAUGAGUCAGCCAAGAAUGGAACCCAAGUCAGAGAGAGAAUGAGAGGAAUGUGUGUGAGAAGCAGACAGACAUCUCCAGAGAGGUCUAGAGAUAGUCAGGGAACCAGGGAGAGGGAGGAAGUGAGAGAAAGAGAUGGUCAGAGAAGUGCAAACAGUGUUUGAGAGUGCACUAAACAAAUUAGGGAGGAUGAAGGUUGGGGGAGACCACUGGGAGUUAGGGAAAGUGGUACGUGUGUCUGGGCCCCAGGCUGUCAGAGCGAUUAGCUUUAAUUGCUCUUCCCUUUGUGGUUAAAUACUCCAUUGGGGAAAUUGCCAGUGAUGCCCUAGGCUGCAGGCUUCCCUGGUUGCCUACUUCCUCAAUUCCGUGCCCAUCAUGUGUGGAUGUAUUAUCAUGCAUGAAGAGGGUCACAGAAUCACAGAGCGCCUCACUCUCUCACACAGAUCCUCACGCACAAUGUCAUGAUGGAUAUCUUCACCAGCUGGUAGGCAGCCAACCACUGAAUCUCCAAGCCACUCCGACCAAACUUACUCUGUCUUUUGUAGCAGGGAUGCUCACCCCUUCCUAAUUGCAGCUCCGAAUAUUCAGAUGGGGACAGUGAAGCACAGAUCUCAGGAGUCCUAAGUAUUCAUGGCUACCACUAAGUUGGAUAGGUGAGUAGGAAAUGCUAGAAGGGGUGAAAGCCUAUAGAAAGGAGGAAAAGAGAGACUGAAAGAUGAAGUAGAAAGGAAAUGCAUGACAAAGAGUGAGAGAGAUGGAGAGAGACAGAAAUAGAAGCAGGGAGUGCCACACCAGAAGAGUGGAAACAGAGAUGGGCUGGGGAGAGUCCUAGGCCCCAUUCCCCUCCUCGCCAUCAGCCGGCCCUCCUCUGCUCUGCCUGAUCCAGUGCCAGCUAUCUCCUGAUGCCCCAUCUUGGGUCUGGCUCUUUCUAGACCAAGGGCUGAAGGCUAAUCCUUGUCCCCAUGCCCAAAGGUAAUCCAUUUUGCUUCUUGGACUGAAGUGAACAUUUUAGGGCCCAGAUGUCCUGCCUCUCGUCACUUCCAGGCUGACCCUGGAGCCUCAGAACCCUCAAUUUCCUUGUUACAGGAGUAAAGACAACCCCCUCCUCCCCCACAAAGCUGGAUAAAAAGCUUAAAGAAGAAAUUAAUUGAGAAUGAUAUUAAAGGAAAUAAACUACAGGACUGCUUGAAUUUGGGGCCCAGUUAUAAUUUAAAAUAGGAAAGCUGGACCCCUACUCUCUCCCUUCCAACCCCUCUGCCUCUCCGUGAUUACUUCCAACUUCAGGCAGAAGACUGACAGACUUGAGUGCCUGGGAGUCCCCUCCUGCCCAAUACAGGGACCUCUAGGUCCUUGCAGCUGUCUGGGAUGGCCCCUCCCCUCAGGCUUAGGCAGCUGCAACAGAUGUGGAAGAGGGACGGGCAGCAACUCUUAAUCUUCAGGCUUCCUUCUCGAAUUUACAGAGGAUUUGGAACCAAACGUUAGAAGGGAUAAUCUACCACGACUUAAUGUCAAAAUGCACAGAAAUUCUUUUGGUGCUGCCACCUCCUCCACAGGUGGUUAUCCCAAUUGCCAGGCUUCUCAAAGCACUCCCAGGGCCUGGCUCUUCUUACCCCAGUGCCCAUGGAGCUCCCACCUGUCCCACCCUAAAAGGUCAGUAUAUAAUGGUCCUUACCUCCUGCCCCUCUUCCCCAGCAUCCUCAGUUGGUUUGACCUUUGUCAGGGCUGUGCCUGGGGCCAGCUUGGAAGGAGAGGGAGGCAGGAAGGAAGGAAGGUGUGAGGAAGCGGUGAGCCUAGCACAGAAAGCUGGGAGGGAAGAGGACUGACUUCCUGGCAGCCGGGGCUCCGGUUCCUGAUUCCUGCCCUGGUAUCCUGUCCCAAGAAUGGCCUCCGCCCAGACUGCCUGGUGAUCCCUGAGCAGCUCUCUGCACUGCUCCAGAAAUCAGGAGGAUUUUUCAGAGCCCAGAGAGCAGAUUUCUCCACGAGCCCUAAGGAAAUCUGAAUCUCUGGUGAGGAAAGUGACAUGGAGGAUGAAGGAAACAAGCUCUGCCAAGCCCCACCAUGGCCAGGCCAGACCAGCCCAGUCAUGGCUGAGUACGGGACCCUCCUGCAAGACCUGACCAACAACAUCACCCUUGAAGAUCUAGAACAGCUCAAGUCGGCCUGCAAGGAAGACAUCCCCAGCGAAAAGAGUGAGGAGAUCACUACUGGCAGUGCCUGGUUUAGCUUCCUGGAGAGCCACAACAAGCUGGACAAAGACAACCUCUCCUACAUUGAGCACAUCUUUGAGAUCUCCCGCCGUCCUGACCUACUCACUAUGGUGGUUGACUACAGAACCCGUGUGCUGAAGAUCUCUGAGGAGGAUGAGCUGGACACCAAGCUAACCCGUAUCCCCAGUGCCAAGAAGUACAAAGACAUUAUCCGGCAGCCCUCUGAGGAAGAGAUCAUCAAAUUGGCUCCCCCACCGAAGAAGGCCUGAGCAAGGGGGAGGAAGAGGAGGAAGGUUGGACCUUCAUCAGACCACUCCCUUCCCCCAUCCUCCAGGAGAGGGGGCAAGGGCAACCCACCAUCUACCCACUUACUAACCUGGUCCUAACCCCCUUACUGUGCGCGUGUGUGUGCGUGUGCGCACGCUCUGGCUGUUUGUCUAUAUGUCUAGCUCAUCUAGUUCCUCUUCUUAAGGGGAUGGGGGUCAGGGGCUAGGGGAGGGGGCUGAGUUUCCCCACUUUAGGAGGAGGUGGGGGCUAUUUCUAUGCAAAUAGAAAUCAGCACAUUCCUCCUACUUCCCUUUCCUCCACUCCCCCCAUAUCUUUAAAGUGUGGAAGCAGAAAGGACCUGCAUUUUCCUACAUUGAGGAGCUGACAUAGGGGUAAGGUAUGGGAGAGGUAGGUGGAUCCAGGGAAAAGCAGUGGGGACGGAAGGCAAAGAGACCACUCAACCCCCACCUGGAAGGGGCAAAGAAAAGCCAGAGUUCCAUGUUUGUACUCCUGUGCUGGACUGUUUCCUGAGUACCAGCAGGUCCCUUUUUGUCUCUCAUGGGCCUAGCAUAGGUAUGAGCCAGGGAUCCUUUCCUGGUCCCUAAGAUCAAACCCCAUGGAGCAGCCAGCGUUAGAUGCCCCCACCCACCUGUACUCUGGAGAGACUGUGCUGGGAACAUGUACCACUGAGCCUGAGAUGGGGAUGAGGGCAGAGAGAGGGGAGCCCCCUCUUCCACUCAGUUGUUCCUACUCAGACUGUUGCACUCUAAACCUAGGGAGGUUGAAGAAUGAGACCCUUAGGUUUUAACACGAAUCCUGACACCACCAUCUAUAGGGUCCCAACUUGGUUAUUGUAGGCAACCUUCCCUCUCUCCUUGGUGAAGAACAUCCCAAGCCAGAAAGAAGUUAACUACAGUGUUUUCCUUUGCACCGAUCCCCACCCCAAUUCAAUCCCGGAAGGGACUUACUUAGGAAACCCUUCUUUACUAGAUAUCCUGGCCCCCUGGGCUUGUGAACACCUCCUAGCCACAUCACUACAGUACAGUGAGUGACCCCAGCCUCCUGCCUACCCCAAGAUGCCCCUCCCCACCCUGACCGUGCUAACUGUGUGUACAUAUAUAUUCUACAUAUAUGUAUAUUAAAACUGCACUGCCAUGUCUGCCCUUUUUUGUGGUGUCUAGCAUUAACUUAUUGUCUAGGCCAGAGCGGGGGUGGGAGGGGAAUGCCACAGUGAAGGGAGUGGCAGAAUCAAAUUGCUACAUAGUCCAAACAAAAAAGAAGGCUUUUUCAAAAAACAUUAAAUUCACAUGCAGUCUCAGAGACUAUUUAGACAAAGUUCAAGUUAGGAGCUUUUAGGAUGUGGGAGUAAAACUUUAAUGGGAGGGGAGGGCUGGCUGCUGGAAGAAGGAAGAAGCCAGACUGGUUAGACAGUACUCUUAACUCCUAGCCCAGCCUAGCGUGCCCUGCCCCUCUGGCCACUGCUGCAGACACCUGCCUUAACACACACACCUCUAGGACUCCACAGUUUUGCCUUAAAGGACCUUCCCAAGUCUCCCUUUCCCUGUCUGGCUUCUCCCUUAAGAAGAGAGAGAUACUUGUAGAAUUGGGUGGGGGGAAUGAGCAUGAACUGUCCUUCCAUUUGGGAUAUGUUACAUUAGAGUGAGAGAGAGAAUAAGGAGCCUUUCUUAUGGAAGAAAUGGGAGAAGAGAGACAGGGUUCUUUUCAGCAGAGUCUAGUAGUUUCUCUGUAAGGCAAAAUAAUCUAAAAAGACUAACCUGCCCACCCACUCCUUAUAUUGCUGUGAGAUUGCCCCUAUCUUGUGCUCUUCUGUCUGCAGUGUGCACGGCCUUGUUCUAACCCGGAAUAAAGGUGAUUGAUUGUAUUGCAA